GAGGAAGGCGCUGGCGGGCAGUGAUGGCGGCUGGUGAUGGGGACGUGAAGCUAGGCACCCUGGGGAGUGGCAGCGAGAGCAGCAACGACGGCGGCAGCGAGAGUCCAGGCGACGCGGGAGCGGCAGCGGAAGGGGGAGGCUGGGCGGCGGCGGCGUUGGCGCUUCUGACGGGGGGCGGGGAAAUGCUGCUGAACGUGGCGCUGGUGGCUCUGGUGCUGCUGGGGGCCUACCGGCUGUGGGUGCGCUGGGGGCGGCGGGGUCUGGGGGCCGGGGCCGGGGCGGGCGAGGAGAGCCCCGCCACCUCUCUGCCUCGCAUGAAGAAGCGGGACUUCAGCUUGGAGCAGCUGCGCCAGUACGACGGCUCCCGCAACCCGCGCAUCCUGCUCGCGGUCAAUGGGAAAGUCUUCGACGUGACCAAAGGCAGCAAGUUCUACGGCCCGGCGGGUCCAUAUGGAAUAUUUGCUGGUAGGGAUGCCUCCAGAGGACUGGCCACAUUUUGCCUAGAUAAAGAUGCACUUAGAGAUGAAUAUGAUGAUCUCUCAGAUUUGAAUGCAGUACAAAUGGAGAGUGUUCGAGAAUGGGAAAUGCAGUUUAAAGAAAAAUAUGAUUAUGUAGGCAGACUCCUAAAACCAGGAGAAGAACCAUCAGAAUAUACAGAUGAAGAAGAUACCAAGGAUCACAAUAAACAGGAUUGAACUUUGUAAACAACCAAAGUCAGGGGCCUUCAGAACUGCAAUUCUUACUCCCUUUCACAGACUGUCCGGAGUCUUUGGGUUUGAUUCACCUGCUGCGAAAAACAUUCAACAAAUUGUGUACAAGAUAAAUUAAUCUCACUAUGAAGAUUUGAAUAACUAGACAUUAUUUAUGCUGCCAAACUCAUUUGUUGCAGUUGUUUGUAAUGUCUAGUGGGGCUUCAUCAUCCUGAAAAGAAGGAGACAGGGAUUUUUUUAAAGAGCAAGAAAGUCACAAUAUUACUUCUUUCCUUCCUUUUUUCCUUCUUUCCUUUCUUCUUUCUCUUUCUUUCUUUUUAAAAUAUAUUGAAGACAACCAGAUAUGUAUUUGCUACUCAAGUGUACAGAUCUCCUCAAGAAACAUCAAGGGACUCCUGUGUCACAUACUGUGUUUUUAUUUUAACAUGGGUGAGGGAGGCGACCUGAUCAGGGGAGGUGGGGGUACACAUCAAUUUGAGUUGUUCAGGCUACUGAAACAUUAAAAUGUGAAUUCCCAAACUUUUCUUUUUGGCUUUGUCAGGGAAAAGAAAAAUAUCUUUAUAAAGAAAUCUUUGGAAAUUAGGAGAAGGAAUUUCAGGUGGGUUUAAGUCAGAGCUAGUUCCCCAACAGAAAGAUCAUUUGAAACCAGUUUUUAUCCCUUCUCUUUCCUUCCCUUUCCCUAAAUCAAAUCAAUAUUAAUUGUGCCUUAUUUCACUUAACAUAGACUUGAAUUAUUUUUAGGGAAAGCCCCUAUAAUGAAUUCAGAAAUCACUACAAGCAGCAUUAAGACUGAAGUUGGAAUAUUCUGUUGACCAUAAAACCUUGAUAUCAUUCUGUGUAUAUAGAAUGUAAAAGGAAUAUUACAGUGUUAACUGCCAUAUAUGUAAUAUACACAAACUCAAUUAGCAUUGUAAUGGCCAAAUGCAUUCCCCCAUGCUUUUCUGUUUUCAAAAAAAUUGAAAAACAAAUCAACUCUUAUCCCCAACAGCUGCCUAAUUUUAGGAGUCUGACCCUCCACAUCUCACUGGUGUGGGUGCAUGGGGCUGUGGAGUGGGUGUCAGUAUGGAUGUGUCUGAAUGUGUGAGGCCUUGGAAGGGACUCUUUCUGCAGAUACUGUAAAUACAAGUACCAUUUUAAUAAAGCAUGUACAAUAAACCAAAAUAAGCUUGAGUUGGACUUUAUAUACAGAACUGUAAGCCAGUGCAUUAUGAUACAGUUGUAAGAUUGUGCAUUUGAUUCAAGAUAAGGAAAAAUCUUGGAAAUGAAAAGCAGGCACUGGUUAACCAAGUUGUACACAUUGUACCACAUUCAGCAUAACUUUAGGAAGAAAUUCCACUUUGUGGAACAUUCUCCAGAAAUCCAAGAUUAUUCAGGUAAGAAUUGGUAUAUUAAAUGUACAUCUUUUUACUUUCUAUUUUGAUGCCAACUGAUUAUACUAGACAAUUAGCACUCCAGGUGGUUAUUGAACACAAAACAGUAAAAGAAUAUUGCACUGAUAGAUACUAAAUUAUUAUUUUAUUAGGUUGAAAAAGCCCUUACUAAAAGCCCCUCAUAUAUCAAUUACUUUAUUUCAUUAUGACUACUUAGGUUCCGGGCUGGGGACAAGUUCACUUAAAAAGGCAAUGUUAUUUAACAGGUCACCAGUUAAGACUUCUGCUUUGUAGAUACAUGCAGAAGCCAUCAAACAAGGGGGAGCUUUUAACUGCAACAAUAAGCUAAAGUAUGUAAAAUACUACAUUCUAUUCAGUCUUGGAGUGUUUUGUAGAAAGUUAUCUUCAGCCAAAUCUUUGCUGAAGACUGGUUGUGGAGUGUUGGUAAAUGCUUUGUGUUUUUAUGUAAAAUAUUUUCUAAACAAAAAAUGUUAAAAGUACAUGUCCUCUGUAGUAAACUGAUAUCUAUAUAUAUGAAUCAUUCAAGCCUAAAGUCUAGUAAUAAACUGUACUUGUGAAUAGAGAAACCCUAAAUAUUCAUGCAGAAAAAAUUAUGCGGUCUGUUAAGAAAAAUGAGUAAUUUGUGUUUUGGACUUGAAAUAAACAGUGUUCUGUAGAUAAUUCCUCAA